AAGGACGUACUCGUCUUGGUGAGAGCGUGAGCUGCUGAGAUUUGGGAGUCUGCGCUAGGCCCGCUUGGAGUUCUGAGCCGAUGGAAGAGUUCACUCAUGUUUGCACCCGCGGUGAUGCGUGCUUUUCGCAAGAACAAGACUCUCGGCUAUGGAGUCCCCAUGUUGUUGCUGAUUGUUGGAGGUUCUUUUGGUCUUCGUGAGUUUUCUCAAAUCCGAUAUGAUGCUGUGAAGAGUAAAAUGGAUCCUGAGCUUGAAAAAAAACUGAAAGAGAAUAAAAUAUCUUUAGAGUCGGAAUAUGAGAAAAUCAAAGACUCCAAGUUUGAUGACUGGAAGAAUAUUCGAGGACCCAGGCCUUGGGAAGAUCCUGACCUCCUCCAAGGAAGAAAUCCAGAAAGCCUUAAGACUAAGACAACUUGACUCUGCUGAUUCUUUUUUCCUUUUUUUUUUUUUUAAAUAAAAAUAUUAUUAACUGGACUUCCUAAUAUAUACUUCUAUCAAGUGGAAAGGAAAUUCCAGGCCCAUGGAAACUUGGAUAUGGGUAAUUUGAUGACAAAUAAUCUUCACUAAAGGUCAUGUACAGGUUUUUAUACUUCCCAGCUAUUCCAUCUGUGGAUGAAAGUAACAAUGUUGGCCACGUAUAUUUUACACCUCGAAAUAAAAAAUGUGAAUACUGCUCCAAAAACAGAGUCACGUAUUCCACUCUCCAACUACCCACAUAUUCCUUUUGCAAUAGCCAUUAGGGCAUCAUUUUGAUAUUUCAUUCUGAUUUCUGAUUCUCUGAUUUCUGAUUCCUAAUGAGGACAGUAGGUCUGGAUCCAAAUUCUCACAGUAAAAUCAAGCAGUAAUUUUCUCUCAUAUCUAUUAGGGAAAGAAAAAUGAUCACAGUCUGCUAAGAGUCUUGAUUUUCUUUGUAAUGCCUCACAUAGUAUGAUAAUCAGUCUCCAAAGCAUCACAUGAUAAUUACAAUGAUACCAUUAACAUGUCAAGGAAAUUAUAUUAUUUAUGGUUGUCAAAAAUUAUGAAGUAGUGUAUGAUUAUAAGCAGAUAUGGCAAAUUUGUUCAGUAAAUCCAUAGAUGACUACAUUUUGAGAAAUACUAAGAUAAUACUAAAAAUUAUGCCUUAGCAUAAUUUGCAUGCAAAAUUGCCCUCUAGUGUUUUUGUUUUGUUUUGAGACAUAGUCUCGCUCUGUUCGCCCAGGCUGGAGUGCAGGGGCACGAUCUCUGCUCACUGCAAGCUCUGCUUCCCGGGUUCACACCAUUCUCCUGCCUCAGCAUCCUGAGUAGCUGGGACUACAGGCACAUGCUGUCACACCCGGCUAAUUUUUUGUAUUUAGUAGAGAUGGGGUUUCACCACGUUAGCCAGGAUGGUCUCCAUCUCCUGACCUUGUGAUCCGCCCACCUCGGCCUCACAAAUUGCUGGGAUUACAGGUGUGAGCCACCACGCCUGGCCGAAAGUUAGUUGUUUUGAACUCAUUUUCUCCUUUUUACCCCUGCCUUUAUCAGCUUCUACCUUCUGGUUUCAUGCUGAGUUCUAGUUGCCUAAAGUCUCCAUUGAAACACUCCUGUUAUAAUUGCCAUAAAAUCAUAAAUCCACUCCCCCUUUCUCCUCCUAGUCAAAAUUUGUAUUCUUUUCAGCAGGUUGGUUUUAAUAAAAAGUAAAUUAAGUUGA